AAGGGGAAAUUUGAAAGCCAAUGUUCAGCUGGACACCUUGCUUAGCGAUUGAGCCCAGGACAGUUACCUUUGCUCUUCCACAGGAGCUUGUGUGUUUUCUCUGGGAGGUGCCUCAAGAGUAGCGAUAGUCCUUGCAGCCCCUGCAAAUCUGUCUGUGACUGGUUGGGCAUCAAGGGAGUUUGCCUGGUUUUCUUGAGGGGCUGGCGAUCACCAGCAUCCUGACCAGGCAGCUCUGCACCCUUCCCGGAAUGCUGACCCAGCCCUUCUGGUGGGACUCUUGUUCCUCCGUCAUCCAGGGAGCUGAGGCUUCUUUCCAGGAUAUGCUCCCCCGCCCCCAGCCAGCGCCAGACCACUCCCCUUGCUGCCUUUGACCCAAUGUCUGCUGGGAGACUUCACGUUCCUUCUGUGGCGUCUGUUCCUCAUUACUGGCUUGUGCCCAUCUCUCUCCUGUUUCUGAACUCAAACUUGCUCCAUUGUGAAACUGGAGCUGGGGCGGAAGCUUUGUUGGAGGAGGCCCUGGGUCUGUCCGCAGGUGCCAUAAUGGAAGGGUUGCUGCUUUGGGCAGGGGUGUGCCUCCCCUGGCCCCUGCUGUGCUGCAACACAUCCUUUUCUGCUGUGUUUCUGAAACCUCCUCUGUCCAUGGUUGAUCCUUCUCACCACCUCUUUUACUGCAGCUCCUCUGACUUCUUCCUUAGCUGUGCUGUUUCACCUCUGUCCUGUUUCUCGCCUGCUUUGCUCUUUGUCCCCUAUCCUUUUGCACUGAGUAGCUGUGGGAUUCCCCGACGCAUCUCCCUGAUGUUUGUGUCUCCAGUCCCCCUGACCUCACCUGGAUCAAGGGAUUCACCAGUCACUGGUAUCCAUAUGUGUGUUUUGGGGGCAUUUGUUCCUAGGGGCUGCCUCUCAGCACUGGCCCUUGUGGGGAUGGGAGAGAACAUGCCACACCACCAGUCGCCACCCUUACUAUUAGCCUGAUCUGAAUCUGCCUGAUGUCAGCCUGUGCUGUGGGAGGGUGUCUCCCUCUGGGCCUGCAGUACCGGGGCUGUUGGGUCUCUCUAGCUCACCUGCUGACCCAGCGUCCCGUUGUGGGGGAUGGCCUGAGCCAGCCAUCUCACAACUUUGUGUGGCUGUGGACAGAGGGCCUUCAUGGGCUUGGGCCACCAGGAACUCCACUCUGUUGGAGCCUGUCAGGGCUCAGCAGUGGGUGGGGUCUGACCUUGAAAGUCUGAAUGUCACGUGGUGCUUUGGGAUCCCUUGUGGGACCCUUGUCCCACGUCAGCACUGGGUGUGCAUUUGAAUUGGGUGUCUCUGCUCAUUGAAAGGGGCCAAUCUUCGUUGGGGAGCAGGAUAGAGCUCUCGCCCUUCCCUUUGGCUCUCAGAGAGGCCUAAGAAAAUUGCAACAAGAGCAGAGGUUGGCUGGUUUGAAGGUGUGGCUCAUCCCACAUUACCAGAGAGACAGUUCCGGAGUCGGGGAUAGUGCUCACGGGCUGGGACUUUCUUCUUUCUUCCUUCUUCUCCUUUUUCUUCUUUCUUCCUUUAUUCCUCUUCUUCUGACAGGGUCUCACUCUGUCGUCCAGGCUAGAGUGGAGUGGUGCUCUCAUGGUUCCCUGCAGCCCCAAAUUCUUGAGCUCAAGCGAUUCUCCUACCUCAGCCUCCUGAGUAGCUGGGACUACAGGCACGCCACCGUGCCUGGCUAAUUUUUAAAUUGUUUUGUGGAGACGAGGUCUCACUGUGUUGCGCACGUUGGUCUCAAACCCCUGGCCUCAAGCGAUCCUCCCACCUCAGUCCCCCAAAGUGCUGGGAUUACAGUUGUGAGCCACUGCACCCAGCCUGGGACUUUGUUCUGAUUCCUCAUUCUUUCCAUUAUAAAGGGUAACCGUAUUAGGCUGCUCAGGCCAUCAUAAACAAGGACCACAGUUUGGAUCGCUUAAACGGCAGAAGUUCAUUUUCUCACCGAUCUGGAGGCUGAAAGUCCAAGGGCAGGGUGUUAACAGGGUUGGUUUCUUCUGAGGGCCGUGAGAGAAAGAUCUGUCCAGGGCCUGCGCCUCGGCUUCUGGAUGGCUGUCACCUCCCUGUGUCUUCACAGGGUCUUUCCUCCUCUUACGGAGACAUCAGUCAUAGUGGAUUAGGGCCCAUGCCAAUGACAUCAUGCUAACUCCGUCACCUCUUUAAAGACCCUGUCUCCAAAUAUAGCCACAUUUUGAGGGCCUUAGGGUUAGUACUUCAACAUAUGAAUUUUGAGAGGACAUAAUUCACCCCGUAACAAUGACAGUGGAGUGAUGUAAGAUGCUGGGCCGGGGCUGUGACCCUACCUCAAGGCUCCAGAAACCCUUUGCAUUUUAAUCUUUUGGUAUCUUCAUGGAGCUGGAGAGGCUGUCCUUUGUGACUUAAUUCCUGGCAGAAUUUUAGAAAAAUUUUUUAUGUUUAAUUUUUGUGCGUACGUAGUAGGUGUAUAUAUUUAUGGGGUACAUGAGGCUUGCAGCACGUAACAGUCACUUCAUGGAAGAUGGGGUAUUCAUCCCCUUCAGCAUUUAUCCUUUGCGUUACAGACUGUUCAGUUAUAUUAUUUUAUUUUAUUUUGACAGAGUUUUACUCUUGUUGCCCAGGCUGGAGUGCAAUGGUGUGAUCUCGUCUCACUAUAACCUCCAGCUCCUGAGUUCAAGCGAUUCUCCUACCUCAGCCUCCUGAGUAGCUGGGAUUACAGGCAUGCGCCACCACGACUGGCUAAUUUUUUGUAUUUUUAGUAGAGACGAGGUUUCACCAUGUUGGCCAGGCUGGUCUCGAAUUCCUGACCUCAGGUAAUCCACCUGCCUCAGCCUCCCAAAGUGCUGGGAUUACUGGCAUGAGCCACCAUGCCUGGCCUCUUUUAGUUAUUUUAAAAUGUGCAAUUAAAUUAUUAUUGACUAUAGUUACCCUGUUGUACUAUCAAAUAGUAGGUCUUAUUCACUCUUUCUAACUAUUUUUUGUACCUAUUAACCAUCCCCAUUUCCCCCCAGCCCCCCACUACCCUUCCCAGCCUCUGGUAACCACCCUUCUACUCUCUAUCUCCAUGAGUUCAAUUGAUUUGAUUUUUAGAUCCCAUAAAUGAGUGAGGACAUGUGAUGUCUGUCUUUCUGUGGCUCUCUUAUUUCACACUUAACAUAAUGAUCCCCAGUUCCAUCCAUGUUGUUGCAAAUGACAGGAUCUUACUCUUUUUUUAUGGCUGAAUAGUACUCCAUUGUGUAUAUAUGCCACAUUUUCUUUAUUCAUUCAUCUGUUGAUGGCCACUUAAGUUGCUUCCAAAUCUUGGCUAUUGAGAACAGAGCUGCAACAAACAUAGGAGUGCAGAUAUACCUCUUCAACAGACUGAUUUCGUUUCUUUGGGUAUAUACCCAGCAGUGGGAUUGCUGGAUCAUAUGGUAGAUCUAUUUUUAGUUUUUUGAGGAAUCUCCAAACUGUUCUCCAUAGUGGUCAUACUAAUUUAUAUUCCCACCAAUACCGUACAAGGGUUCCCUUUUCUCCACUUCCUCACCAGCAUUUGUUGUUGCCUGUCUUUUGGAUAAAAGCCAUUUUCACGGGGGUGAGAUGAUAUCUCAUUGUAGUUUUGAUUUGCAUUUCUCUGGUGAUCAAUGAUGUCGAGCACCUUUUCAUGUGCCUGUUUGCCACUCGUAUGUGUUUUCCUUGAGAAAUGUCUGUUUAAAUCUUUUGUCCAUUUUAAAUUUGGAUUAUGAGAUUUUUUUUCCUAUAAAGUUGUUUGAGCUCUUUAUAUAUUCUGGUUAUUAGUCCCUUGUCAGAUGGGUAAUUUGCCGAUUUUUCUCCCAUUCUGUGGGUUUUCUCUUCACUUUGUUGAUUGUUUCCUUUGCUGUGCAGAAGCUUUUUAACUUGAUGUGAUCCCGCCUGUCCAUGUUUGCUUUGGUUGCCUGUGCUUGUGGGGUAUUGUUCAAGAGCCUGGCAGAAUUUUAUUCAGAUGUUUGAAUUGGAGCUUACAUCCUUUCUGAGAUCAUUUCUUCCAUGUAUAAAAUUGAGUUGCGAGCCACUUCACAAGGUUUUGUGCAGAGCAACGAUAAUAGCUACUGUUCAGGAAGUGCUUACUGUGUGCCUACCACUUAAUUCUCAGCCCAAGCCUUAUUAUUAACCCCGUUUUACAGAUGCAGAAGCUGAGGCACACGAAGGUUAAAUAAUUGGUGGUCAUACAAUUAACAAGUAUCCAGAACUGGAAUUUGAAUGCAGGCCCCUGAUCUAAAGUCUGGGCUUAUCUCCUCUAUGGAUGUAAAGUGCCCAAUGCUAUCCUGGGCACAUAGAGCCUUGGAAAACACCUCCCUCCUGCGCGCAGGGUGAUGUGAGCAGAGCCCAGGAAUGCCUUAUGUGGAUCGGCAGAACCGAAUCUGUGGGUUUCUGGACAUCGAGGAGCAUGAGAACAGCGGCAAGUUUCUGCGGAGGUACUUCAUUCUGGACACCCAGGCUAACUGCCUCCUCUGGUAUAUGGACAACCCCCAGAAUCUGGCAAUGGGGGCAGGAGCUGUUGGAGCUUUGCAGCUGACCUACAUCUCGAAGGUGAGCAUAGCUACCCCAAAACAGAAACCAAAAACUCCAUUUUGCUUUGUUAUCAAUGCCCUGUCUCAGAGAUAUUUCCUUCAAGCCAAUGAUCAGAAAGAUAUGAAGGACUGGGUUGAAGCCCUGAACCAAGCCAGCAAGAUCACCGUUCCCAAAGGUGGGGGCCUACCCAUGACCACUGAAGUUCUCAAGAGCUUAGCAGCUCCUCCAGCCCUGGAGAAGAAGCCACAGGUGGCCUACAAGACGGAGAUCAUUGGAGGGGUGGUGGUCCACACACCCAUCAGCCAGAACGGUGGGGAUGGGCAGGAAGGGAGUGAGCCCGGGUCCCACACCAUCCUUCGAAGGUCUCAGAGUUACAUCCCCACGUCAGGCUGCCGUGCUUCCACUGGGCCUCCCCUCAUUAAGAGUGGUUACUGCGUGAAGCAAGGGAAUGUGCGGAAGAGCUGGAAACGUCGCUUCUUUGCACUUGAUGACUUUACCAUCUGCUACUUCAAGUGUGAGCAGGACCGAGAACCACUGCGCACCAUAUUUCUUAAGGAUGUUCUGAAGACCCAUGAAUGUCUGGUCAAGUCUGGUGAUCUCUUAAUGAGGGACAACCUGUUUGAAAUAAUAACAAGCUCCAGGACCUUCUACGUACAGGCAGACAGUCCAGAAGACAUGCACAGCUGGAUUAAGGAGAUUGGCGCAGCUGUCCAGGCCCUCAAGUGCCACCCCAGAGAAACGUCCUUUUCUAGAUCCAUUUCUUUGACCCGACCUGGAAGCUCCAGCCUUUCAAGUGGGCCCAACUCUAUCCUGUGCAGGGGGCGGCCACCUUUGGAGGAAAAGAAAGCCCUCUGCAAAGCCCCCUCUGUGGCCUCCUCCUGGCAGCCCUGGACACCUGUCCCCCAGGCUGGGGAGAAGCUGCUUCCACCUGGAGACACUUCAGAGGACUCCUUGUUCACGCCUCGUCCUGGGGAGGGCAGCGCUCCUGGGGUGCUGCCCAGCUCCCGGAUAAGGCACAGAUCGGAGCCCCAGCACCCCAAGGAGAAGCCGUUUAUGUUCAACCUUGAUGAUGAAAACAUACGGACCUCUGAUGUGUGAUGGAGCACAGUGCCAUGGGAGGGAGGGAGGGAGGGAGGACUUGAGAGAAGGAGGCUGUGACUCAGUUUCUCUACCUUGUUGGAGGGUAGUCAGAGGCCUUUAUGUCACUCAUAUUCCUGUGGAUGCUCUUUGGGAGGGAGGGGCCCAUCCAGCUGGGCUGUGUGUGUGUGUGUGUGUGUGUGUGUGUGUGUGUGUAAUAUCAACGCAGUGUAUUUAAUUUGGGGAAGUCACUAGGUUAGAACUGUAGGCAUACUCAGUGGAGAGGAAGCUACCUAUUCUAUUCUAACUAUUCUGAGGUCUUCCUGGAGAGGGAUUGUUUUAGCAGCUCCUCUCCAGAGGGGGCUGGAAGUCCAGUUUCACCAAUGACCAAGUUUUAUUUCCUUGUCCUUGUUUUAGUUUUUUCAUUUUGUUUUCAGUCCAGGUGCCUCGCAGCUCUUUUGGAAUGGGCCAGCAUUAGUCUAAUUUUAAGCGCUAUGUGUUUUGUACCCUUGCAAACUUGCUUUCUCUUUCUUCUUGCUGUUGCCCUUUGAAUGAAGCCUUGUGUGCUUGCAUGAUCAGACCCUGUAAUAGGAUGAAUUUCCAUGCACUUAACAUGAAGAGAUACAAAAAGAAUCUAGAGAGAGAUAUAUAUUUUUAAUGAAAUAGAAGCUUGGCAUAGAAACAUUGAUUUAGAUGUUAUGAGUUGCUGGCCAGAGAUUCCUCAGAUAAAAGAGCCUAGAAAAUUGAGUUUUGAGCGGGCAUGGUGGCUCACGCCUGUAAUGCCAGUAGUUUGGGAGGCUGAGGCGGGUGGAUCACCUGAGGUCAGGAGUUCGAGAUCAGCCUGGCCAACAUGGUGAAACCCCGCCUCUACUAAAAAAUAUGCAAAAUUAGCCGGGCGUGGUGGUGCAGGCCUGUAAUCCCAGCUACUCAGAGGCUGAGGCAGGAGAUUCACUUGAACCCAGGAGGUGGAGGUUGCAGUGAGCCAAGAUCGCGCCAUUGCACUCCAGUCAGGGCAACAAGAGUGAAACUCCGUCUCAAAAUAUAAAAGAAAAUUGAGUGUCCCACCCAAAUUUUAGGGCGUACCUCCUUCCAUUUGAUAAGAAGAUGCUAUUUCCAGUGUCCCUGGGAGAAUUCUUCCAUCCAGUUUAUAUGGUGAAUUGCCACCAGCGUUCCCUAAAGGAAGAGAGAACUUAGCUUAUUUCUGUCUGUGACUUUUAUCAGCUAGAUCAGUUAAUUGUAUUUUUAAAUUAAAAAUUAGUAACUAGAGGAAGAGACUAAGAGAACUAUUUUUACCUGAGUAAAUGCUCUCCUCUUCUUGUGUCCAAAUCUAAUGCAGAGGUGAAAACACUUGAUGAGAAAAUCCUUUGUGGCUUGAGGGGAAUCAUGUUUCUUUCAGGACGUGUUGUUUCCCUGAAGUCUAUGUCACACUGAGAACUUUUUCUGACUGCACUGCUUUGGAGCUAUUCAUUUAAAUUGAGUUUGGCCUAGUUUUCCUGGUAUAAAACAGGAAAUCUACAUUGUUCCCUCUUUCUCUCCCUUCCAUCCCUUCCCCUGCCUUUCCUAUACACGCUGGUGUGCUUUUGCCCUCAGAAAUUCUUGGUUUGGGAGUUAUGUAUUUUUGAGUGAUCGAGGUUAUGACAUACUUGGAGCGGCAUGAUUUCAAGAAGCCAUUCCAAAUUCUUAUAGCUCCUUAGCUCUGGUUUUACUCUCGUAUUUUCCCCAAGAAAAUUUUUUGGCUAUUCAAAGAAAGCACAAAAUAUGUGAUGUGGAACUCAUGAAAAUAGGGACUUUUGAUAUCUCUUUAAAUAUUCCCUGACUCACGGAAAAGAUGUCCUCUUUUGGUGUAUACAUUGUGAAAAUCUACCCAUUUAUCUCUCUCUCUCUCUUUUCUUUUAAAUAAAUUAUCUGAUAAGGCCGGCAAGGUGGCUCACGCCUGUAAUCCCAGCACUUUGGGAGGCCGAGGCGAGCGGAUCACGAGGUCAGGAGAUCGAGACCGCGGUGAAACCCCGUCUCUACUAAAAAUACGAAAAAAAAAUUAGCCGGGCGCAGUGGCAGGCGCCUGUAGUCCCAGCUACUUGGGAGGCUGCGGCAGGAGAAUGGUGUGAACCUGGGAGGCGGAGCUUGCAGUGAGCCAAGAUCGCGCCACUGCACUCCAGCCUGGGCGACAGAGCAAGACUCCAUCUCAAAAAAAAAAUUAUCUGAUAGGUUACUAUUGCUAAAUUAAUUGGCCAUUAUAAUAAGCUGAUUUGUUUCUUAUUCAGCAAGAUCUCUUUUGAGAAUGUGACAAAUUAAACAUACAUAGAAUCCAUAUGGUAUUAUCCUGAUAAAGGGAAACGAGGACACUAAGACUGUCAAAUGGAAAUCUUCUUGUCAAUUGGCAAACACUUGGGAAUUCCACAUUAGAGCAUUGCUUGUUUUUAAUUUUUUUUUUUUAAUUUUUAAAAGACAGGGUCUCACUCUCUUACCCAGGCUAGAGUGCAGUGGUGUGAUCAUAGUUCAUCAUAACUUUGAAUCUCUGGGCUUAAGCAAUCCUCCCAUGUUAGCUUCCCAAGUAGCUAGGACUACAGGGUUGUGCUACCACGCCUGGCUAAUUUUUAAUUUUUUUUUAUCUACAGAGCCUGGCUAUGUUGCCCAGGCUCUCUCAAACUCCUGGCCCAAGUGAUCCUCCUGCCUUGGCCUCCUAAAGUGUUGGGAUUACAGGUGUGAGCCACUGCACCUAGCCAGAACAUCGUUAAUGUAGUUCAAUAUGAGAUAAAUUAUUAUCUUCAAUGAAACAAGCUCUAAAAGCAUUCCAUUCCUAAAUUGUAUUUCAAACUUCCUAUUUUGUUGAUAUUUCUUAACUUCUGGCCAGUUUUGGACCAUAAUCUUUUAAUGUGAACCAAAGAUGGUACGUAUUUGACCAAAGCAGUUAGUUUUAAAUGUAUAAAAUUGAACCAAAUGGAAAAAAUAGGUUGGGGAUGCAGUAUAGAUUAGUGACUAAGUGCAUAGGCUCUGGAGUAAAUCUGAGUUUUUUUUUUUUUAAAGGAACUAAAAAAUGUACUGCAUUUUCUUUGUGGAAUAAAAGCCUUGCCUGAGUUGUGCUAUUUUCAUAAGGCUUUUGAAGUGGUCUUGACCCACUGUGUGUAACAGUAUUUCAGGUGGUCCUCCCCAUGGCUGAAUAAUGCCAUCCAUUAUUCUUUAAUUUUUAUUUUUAGAAACAGUGUUUCACUCUGUCACCCAGGCUGGAGUGCAGUGGCCUGAUCAUGGCUCACUGCAGCCUGGACCUCCUGGGCUCAAGUGAUCUUCCUGCCUCACAGCCUCCCAAAGUACUCAGAUUAUAGGUGUGAGCCACCACGCCUGGCCACCAUCUAUUACUUUUGAAAUCUUCAAAAGACUUGCUUACUCAAUGUCAGCUGAUGGUUGGUAAAAAUAAUUUGGCCUUUAGUGUUAAGUGAGACAUCAUAAGGGUAUUGAGGUAUACAUUAUGGAGAUUGAUGUCAGGUCAGAAUAUUGGAGUUAUACAUCUAUUUCUGAGUUGAAUACUCAGCUCCCACGAGAAAGAAAGUAGUUUUAAGGUCCAGCUUCUUAGUCUACUUGAAGCAAAUUUUUUUUCUUUUAUAUUUCUGAAUAUAAAUAUACUCUUAUAUGGGCUAAAAAGACCCCAUGAAUAAAUAGCAGGUUCAGUAGUUGAGGAGUGGAGUUUAGUAGGUUUGUUUUCAGUAUAAAUUAGAUAACAUGUGGAGGUCACAGCAUUUUGGAAAUUGAGUGUCCCCAAGUGAGCUUUGUUUAUAAACUUUCAAAAUGUCGGAAGUGGACAGGUUUGUUAAAUCUUGUCUGCCAGCACCCUUUUCUUCCUUUGUUCCUUUUCCUCUCUGUGUUAUUGCCUGCGGCAGCCAGUCCUUCAUACUAGAUAGAGUUCAGAUAAAGCAAACGUUUGGCAAAAACAUACUGUUUGACCUCCUCCCCCUCUGCUUAUGAAGGGGUAGCAUGAUUCUGUGUUUUAAAGCAGUGAUGUUUCAGCUGUGAAAUGCACUCGCUGUAAGCUCUAGGCUGAGUGCAUGGAAACUGUUACGCUUCUCAUUUUAUGUGAUCUCCUAAUUGGUAUGUAGCAAAAAUUUUCUAAAACUGUUUUGUGGCUUGUUUUGUAAUAAAACCAUGUGAAAUACUGAAA